GUGCCGAUUUAGCUGCCGCCGCGCCUUGGAGUCCUGAGGAACUUGGCUAGGCUGGCCCCGAGCGGAACCAGAGAAUGCUGAGGCUCUAACCAUGGAAUAUUCGGAAUGUCCCAUUCUAUGAAGGAGGUUUGCUGGCUGCAACAGGAAUAUUCAUGAACAUGGAGGGGUUGGUCAUGUUCCAGGAUCUGUCUAUAGACUUCUCUCAGGAGGAAUGGGAGUGCCUGGACGCUGCUCAGAAGGACUUAUACAGAGAUGUAAUGAUGGAGAACUACAGCAGCCUGGUCUCACUAGGUCUCUCUAUCCCAAAGCCUGAUGUGAUUUCCUUACUGGAGCAAGGGAAAGAGCCCUGGAUGGUUUCAAGGGACGUGCUGGGAGGAUGGUGCCGAGACUCGGAGUUUAGAUGUAAGACCAAAGAUUCAUGUUUGCCAAAAGAAAUCUAUGAAGUAACAUCAUCUCAGUGGGUGAGAAUGGAAAAAUGUCAUAGCCUUGUGGGCUCCAGUGUCAGAGAUGACUGGGAAUGCAAAGGCCAGUUUCAGCACCAAGAUAUAAAUCAGGAGCGAUAUUUGGAAAAAGCAAUAAUGACUUAUGAAACAACACCAACUUUCUGCCUACAGACAUCUCUCACUCUGCAUCAUCGGAUUCAUCCUGGAGAGAAACUGUAUAAAUCCACAGAAUGUAUGGCUUUUAAGUAUGGCUCAGAACUUACACAACAGCAAGAAACCCAUACUGGUGAAAAACUCUAUAAAUGUAAGGAGUGUGGGAAGGCCUUUCAUCACUUUUCCUAUCUUGUUAAACAUCAGAGAAUUCAUACUGGGGAAAAGCCCUGUGCAUGUAAAGAAUAUGGAAAAGCUUUUAUUUCUGGCUCACAUCUUAUUCAACACCAGAAAAUGUAUACAGAUGAGAGACCUCAUGAGUGUCAGGAAUCCGUGAAGGCCUUUAGACCGUCUGCACAUCUUAUUCAACAUUGGAGAAUUCAUACUGGUGACAAACCUUAUGAAUGUAAAGAAUGUGGGAAAUCUUUUACUUCUGGCUCAACACUAAAUCAACAUCAGCAAAUUCACACUGGUGAGAAACCCUAUCAUUGUAAGCAAUGUGGAAAAUCUUUUACUGUUGGCUCAACACUAAUUCGACACCAGCAAAUUCACACUGGUGAGAAACCGUAUGAUUGUAAGGAAUGUGGAAAAUCUUUUGCUUCAGGCUCAGCACUAAUUCGACAUCAGCGAAUUCACACUGGUGAGAAACCCUAUGACUGUAAGGAAUGUGGAAAAUCUUUUACUUUUCACUCAGCUCUAAUUCGACAUCAGCGAAUUCACACUGGUGAGAAACCCUAUGAUUGUAAGGAAUGUGGGAAAUCUUUUACUUUUCGCUCAGGGUUAAUUGGACACCAGGCAAUUCACACUGGUGAGAAACCCUAUGAUUGUAAAGAAUGUGGAAAAUCUUUUACUGCUGGCUCAACACUAAUUCAACAUCAGCGAAUUCACACUGGUGAGAAACCCUAUGAUUGUAAGGAGUGUGGGAAAUCUUUUGCUUCGGGCUCAGCACUACUUCAACAUCAGCGGAUUCACACUGGUGAGAAACCCUAUUGUUGUAAGGAAUGUGGAAAAUCUUUUACUUUUCGCUCAACACGCAAUCGACACCAGCGAAUCCACACUGGUGAGAAACCCUAUAAUUGUAAAGAAUGUGGAAAAUCUUUUGCUUCUGGCUCAGCACUACUUCAACAUCAGCGAAUUCACACUGGUGAGAAACCCUAUCAUUGUAAGGAAUGUGGAAAAUCUUUUACUUUUCGCUCAGGGCUAAUUGGACAUCAGGCAGUUCACACUGGUGAGAAACCCUAUGAUUGUAAAGAAUGUGGAAAAUCUUUUACUUCUCGCUCAGCACUAAUUCAACAUCAGCGAAUUCACACUGGUGAGAAACCCUAUCACUGUAAGGAAUGUGGAAAAUCUUUUACUGUUGGCUCAACACUACUUCAACAUCAGCAAAUUCACACUGGUGAGAAACCUUAUGAUUGUAAGGAAUGUGGGAAGGCCUUUAGACUUCGUUUACGACUUACUCAACAUCAACAAAUCCAUACUGGUGAGAAACCUUAUCAAUGUCAGGAAUGUGGGAAAGCCUUUGUCAGUGUCUCAGGACUCACCCAACAUCACAGAAUUCACACUGGUGAGAAACCCUAUGAAUGUCCGGACUGUGGGAAGGCCUUUAGACAGCGUACAUACCUUAAUCAACAUCGGAGAAUUCAUACUGGUGAGAAACCUUAUGAAUGUAAAGAAUGUGGGAAAUCUUUUACUUUCUGCUCAGGACUAAUUCAACAUCAGCAAAAUCACACUGAUGAGAAACCCUAUGAUGGUAAGGAAUGUGGGAAAUCUUUUACUUCUCACUCAACACUAAUUCAACAUCAGCAAAUUCACACUGGUGAGAAACCCUAUGAUUGUAAGGAAUGUGGGAAAUCUUUUACUUCUCACUCAACACUAAUUCAACAUCAGCAAAUACACACUGGUGAGAAGCUCUAUGAUUGUAAGGAAUGUGGGAAAUCUUUUACUUCUCAUUCAACACUAAUUCAACAUCAGCCACUUCACACUGGUGAGAAACCUUAUCAUUGCAAGGAAUGUGGGAAAUCUUUUACUCUUCGCUCAGCACUAAUUCAACAUCGGCCAGUUCACACUGGUGAGAAACGCUACAGUUGUAAAGAAUGUGGGAAAUCUUUUACUUCUCGCUCAACACUAAUUGAACAUCAGCGAAUUCACACUGGUGAGAAACCCUAUCAUUGUAAGGAAUGUGGAAAAUCUUUUGCUUUUCGCUCAGCAAUAAUCCAACAUCGGCGAAUUCACACUGGUGAGAAACCCUAUGAUUGUAAGGAAUGUGGCAAGGCCUUUAGACGUCGUUCAAAACUUACUCAACAUCAACGAAUCCAUACUGGUGAGAAACCUUAUCGAUGUCAUGAAUGUGGAAAAGCCUUUGUCCGUUUCUCAGGACUCACCAAACAUCACAGUAUUCACACUGGCGAGAAACCCUAUGAAUGUAAGACAUGUGGGAAGUCCUUCAGACAGCGUACACACCUUACUCUACAUCAGAGAAUUCAUACCGGUGACAGACCUUAUGAAUGUAAAGAAUGUGGGAAAUCUUUUACUUGCGGCUCAGAACUAAUUCGACAUCAGCGAACUCACACUGGUGAGAAACCUUAUGAUUGUAAGGAAUGUGGGAAGGCCUUUAGAUGUCCUUCACAACUUAGUCAACAUAAACGAAUCCAUACUGGUGAGAAAACUUAUCAAUGUCCGGAAUGUGGGAAAGCCUUUUUCUAUGCCUCAGGACUCAGCCGACAUCAGAGUGUUCACACUGGCGAGAAACCCUAUGAAUGUAAGACAUGUGGGAAGGCCUUUAAACAGCUUACACAGCUUACUCGACAUCAGAGAAUUCAUGACCUAACAUAAUUAAUGUAGGAAACUGUUCUCAUGCCAUUUGUCAUGGAUCAUCAGCAGAUUCCAUAUGUGGGUCAAAUACAAUGGAUGUGUAUUACUUCAUAUUCACUUUUUCCAGAAUUACGACUUUUUUUUUUUUUUUUGAGACGGAGUCUUGCUCUGUCGCCCAGGCUGGAGUGCAGUGGCGCUAUCUCGGCUCACUGCAAGCUCUGCCUCCUGGGUUCAUGCCAUUCUCCUGCCUCAGCCUCCCUAGUAGCUGGGACUACAGGUACCUGCCACCACGCCUGGCUAAUUUUUUUGUUUUUGUAUUUUUAGUAGAGACAGGGUUUCACUGUGUUAGCCAGGAUGGUCUCGAUCUCCUGACCUGGUGAUCCACCCACCAAAAUUAGGACAUUUAAUACUGAAAGAAAUUGAUAAUGAAUGUAGAUGAGUUUUCUAUCAUGAUUCAAAGCUUAUUGAAGUUAUACAAAUUCAUAUUAGAGAAUGUGGUCAAUGACAAAAGACAACCAUUUACUACCUACGUGACAUUAGGCUAGUUAUGUAAAUUCUCUGUGCCAAAAUUACUAAUUGAUAAAAUGUUGAUGGCAAUAGUUGUUUUUGUGUAUUUUUUGUUUGUUUGUUUUGUUUUGAGACAGAGUCUUGCUCUGUUGCCCAGGCUGGAGUGCAGUGGUGCUAUCUUGGCUCACUGCAACCUCUGCCUCCUGGGUUCAAGUGAUUCUCCUGCCUCUGCCUCCUGAGUAGCUCAGAUUACAGGCAUGCACCACCAUGCUUGGCUAAUUUUUGUAUUUUUAGUAGAGACGGGGUUUCACUGUGUUGGUCAGGGUGGUCUCAAACUUUUGACCUCGUGAUCCCCCUACCUCGGCCUCCCAAAGUGCUGGGAUUACAGGUGUGAGCCACCACGCCUGGCUAGUAAUAGUUUUUUUAUAAUAAAUAAGUGUGACUAUAUUUUUCAUGUUUGACUACUGACUUUGUUUUAAGCUUCGCCUUCCCUGUCUAUUUCCCUGUCUACUUUAGCCCAUAACUGCAAAGGUGGCUAAGAAAGUCCUUGCUGGAAAGAAAGCAAGCAAAACUAAAGUCUGUGCGCACCUUCUCCUUUGGAUCCAGUGGGCAAUUUAUAUUAGAAAUUCCAAGCCGGGCGUGGUGGCUCACGCCUGUAAUGCCAGCACUUUCGGAGGCUGAGGUGGGUGGAUCACCUGAGGUUAAGAGUUCAAGACCAGCCUGGCCAACAUGUUGAAACCCCAUCUCUACUAAAAAUACAAAAUCAGCCAGACAUGGUGGCAUAUGCCUGUAAUCCCAGCUAUUCAGGAGGCAAGGCUGGAGAAUCGCUUGAACCUGGGAGGCGGAUGUUGCAGUGAGCCAGUCAGUGGAGCAGUCAGAACACACACAGUGUUUAUCAAUUAAGUUUGUAGUCAGAACACACACCAUGUUUAUCAAUUAAGUUUGCUGUCUUAUAUGGACACAGUUUGUGAUGCCCUAAAACAAGUAGUGGUGCCUAAGAUAAUCAUAGGCCACCAUAACAGAUAUAACAACAAUGAGAAAGUUGAAAUAUUGUUGGGAUCAUCCAAAUAUGACACAGAUACAAAGUGAGCACAUGCUGGUGAAUAAAUGGAGCCAAUAGACUUGUUCACUGCAUGGUUACGUCAGAGGCGUGUAAACCAGAGCAACUUCUUCUUGAAUAGGAGCUGUGUAAAGUAACACUGAAACCUACUGGACUGCAUUCCUAGACAGAUAAGUCAUUCUAAGUCACAAGAUGAGAUAUGAGGUCAGCAUAAGAUACAGGUCAUAAAGACCUUGCUGAGAAAACAUCUUGCAGUAAAGAAGUCGGCCAAAUCCAAGAUGGUGACAAGAGUGACCUCUGGUCGUCCUCACUGCUAUACUCCCAGCAGCACCAUGACACCCAGCUAAGUUUUUAUUUUUUAUUUCAGUAGAGUUGGAGUCUUGCUUUGUUACCCAGGCUGGUCUUGAAUUCCUGUCUUCAAGCAAUCUUCCCACCUUAUGAAUAUAAAGAAUGGCCCACCUUGUCCUCUCAAAGUGCUGGGAUUACAAUCAUGAGCCACUGCACCUGGGACUUUCUUUUUCUUUUUUCUUUUUUUUUUUUUUGAGAUGGAGUUUUGCUCUUGUUGCCCAGGCUGGAGUGCAAUGGCACGAUCUUGGCUCACUGCAACCUCCGCCUCCCAGGUUCAAGCGAUUCUCUUGACUCAGCCUCCUGAGUAACUGGGAUUACAGGCAUGCUCCACCAUGCCCGACUAAUUUUUGUAUUAUUUAGUAGAGACGGGGUUUCUCCAUGUUGGUCAGGCUGGUCUCUGAACUCUGGGCAGGACUAAUUUAGAUAAGGUAGUCAGGAAAGGCAUUUCUUACAAGGUGGUAUUUGCAUGAAUGUAGACAUAUGGUUGCAUUUUAUUAUAUGUAAAUUACACUUCAAUAAAGUUGAUGAAAAAAAUCUUACCUCAUCGUCUAUGCACUUCGGAUUGUUGUAUUUCAUUCUAUUUAAAUUACACUUGCGUUUAAAAAAUUUAACACUUCUCUAAAACAUAUCUGUUGAUUUGUACUUUUACUAAUAUGCUUAUGGAUGAUUUAUAUACACACACACACACACACAUAUCUUUUAAGAAGGUUAUUUUAAGGUUAAUCAAUUGAGGCUUUGUCUCAAUUGAUUUUUUUUGAGACAGUCUCGUUCUGUCGCCCAGGCUGGAGUGCAGUGGCGUGAUCUCGACUCACUGCAAGCUCCACCUCCCAGGUUCACGCCAUUCUCCUGCCUCAGCCUCCCUAGUAGCUGUGACUACAGGUGCCCGCCACCACGCCUGGCUAAUUUUUUGUAUUUGUAGUAGAGACGGAAUUUCACCAUGUUAGCCAGGAUGGUCUCAAUCUCCUGACCUCAUGACCCGCCCACCUCGGCCUCCCAAAGUGCUGGGAUUACAGGCGUGAGCCACCCCGCCCGGCUCAAUUGAUUCUUUUGUCUCAAUUUGUAGUCAGUUGAGGUUUGUCUCAAUUUAUGGAAACAAAUCAAAUGUUUGUUCUCAAAUUCUUACUCUGUCAUUUAUUAUUCUCCAUGUUUUUGUAACUGCUUCCUUGGAGAUAUUUAAACAUAAAUAUAUACAGAGAGGGUGAAGAUGGAGGAGUGCUUUUUACAGUUCACAGUUGUCUUUUUCAUGUGUGACAGGUUUUUGCUGUGUUGCCCAGGCUGGAGUGCAAUGCCACAAUCUUGGCUCACUGCAGCCUCAACUUCCCGGGCUCAAUCGAUCCCCCACCUCAGCCUCCCGAGUAGCAAGGACUACAGGCGCACACCACCACACCUAGCUAAUUUUUGUAUCUUUUGUAGAGACAGGGUUUCACCAUGUUGUCCAGGCUGGUCUUGAACUCUUGGGCUCAAUUGGUCCUAGCACCUCAGCCUCCUAGGUGCUGGGAUUACAGGUGUGAGCCACUGUGUUCAGCCAAUACUCUUAACGUUUUUACUUUUCACUUUUAAAAAUUAACUCUUUUUAUGAAAAAAGUAGAAUUUUUUAAAGAGCAGAGAAAAGCACAAUGAAGACAGAAAGAUCACCUGUAUAUUCUUAUUGACCAAAGAUGAUCUAUUUGGGGUAAAUCCUUUUUUUUUUUUUUGAGACGGGAGUUUUGCUAUUGUUGCCCAGGCUGGAGUGCAAUGGCACGAUCUCGGCUUACCGCAACCUCUGCCUCCCAGGUUUAAACAAUUCUCCUGCCUCAGCCUCCUGAGUAGCUGGGAUUACAGGCAUGCACCACCACGCCCGGCUAAUUUUGUAUUUUUAAUAGAGACAGGGUUUCUCCAUGUUGAGGCUGGGCUUGAACUCCAGACCUCAGGUGAUCUGACUGCCUCGGCCUCCCAAAGUGCUGGGAUUACAGGCAGGAUCCACGUGCCCGGCCGGUAAAUCCUUUUAAUAGAGGAGUUUCAAUAUUUCUCCUCUGCCAUAGUAUUAGAAAGAAAAGAAUCAUUAUUGACAUCUUUACGACAUUGAGUUUUUCUCUUGUACCUGGUGUGUCUUUAUUUCAGUAGGUAUUCUUUUAUGUGCUUUAGUAAGUCUUUAUAUUUUUAGCAUAAAAGUGUACACAUUUCUUGUUUUACUUAUUUCUAGAUACUUAAUGGCUUUUGUUUAUAAUAUGAUUGGGAUAUUUUUUCUGUUGUGUAAUUGAUUACUAUUACUAUGUACUAAACUGUUGGUUUUUGUCUAAGGAUUGUAACAUUGAUGAACUACUUUAGUAGAUGAAAUGGUUUCUUCAUGAGAUUGAAUUGUCUAAAGAGAUGUUGGUAUUAUUUGUAAAUAAAAGUAUUUGCCUAUUCCUUUC